CCAAGUAGCUGGGAUUACAGGUGCCCACCACCCCGCCUGGCAAAUUUUUGUAUUUUUAGUAGAGACAGGGUUUCACCAUGUUGGCCAGUCUGGUCUUGACUCCCUGACCUCAGGUGAUCCACCCCCCUUGGCCUCCUAAAGUGUUGGGAUUACAGGCGUGAGCCACCUCACCCGGCCCCUAACUCUAUUUCCUAUGCCCAAUCCCAAGUGUAGGCCACAAGGACUGCAAGUCCUAGUGCUGAGCUGGGCCCGGAGACAGUAGACUGCGGGGGGCACAGGACCUACUGAGACACCAGUCUGGGCAGCUCAGGGAGUGCUGGCGUCACCCCUUCCCUAAUCCCAGGCUGCAUGGCUAACGGUUCCUAUCUGCAGUCCCAGCCUUCCACUUCCGAGUUCUUCUCUCAGACCACAGUCCCAGCAACCCAGAAUUUGGAUUGGAGUCUGGAAGAAAUGCAGAAUGAUUAAACGACCACCUUUCCAUUUGAAGUCCCCAUCCCUGAAUCUUCACGGGUGUGCCCAAGCUCCCCUCCCAGUUCCCCCAGGGACGGCCACUUCCUGGUCCCCGACGCAACCAUGGCUGAAGAACAACCGCAGGUCGAAUUGUUCGUGAAGGCUGGCAGUGAUGGGGCCAAGAUUGGGAACUGCCCAUUCUCCCAGAGACUGUUCAUGGUACUGUGGCUCAAGGGAGUCACCUUCAAUGUUACCACCGUUGACACCAAAAGGCGGACCGAGACAGUGCAGAAGCUGUGCCCAGGGGGGCAGCUCCCAUUCCUGCUGUAUGGCACUGAAGUGCACACAGACACCAACAAGAUUGAGGAAUUUCUGGAGGCAGUGCUGUGCCCUCCCAGGUACCCCAAGCUGGCAGCUCUGAACCCUGAGUCCAACACAGCUGGGCUGGACAUAUUUGCCAAAUUUUCUGCCUACAUCAAGAAUUCAAACCCAGCACUCAAUGACAAUCUGGAGAAGGGACUCCUGAAAGCCCUGAAGGUUUUAGACAAUUACUUAACAUCCCCCCUCCCAGAAGAAGUGGAUGAAACCAGUGCUGAAGAUGAAGGUGUCUCUCAGAGGAAGUUUUUGGAUGGCAACGAGCUCACCCUGGCUGACUGCAACCUGUUGCCAAAGUUACACAUAGUACAGGUGGUGUGUAAGAAGUACCGGGGAUUCACCAUCCCCGAGGCCUUCCGGGGAGUGCAUCGGUACUUGAGCAAUGCCUACGCCCGGGAAGAAUUCGCUUCCACCUGUCCAGAUGAUGAGGAGAUCGAGCUCGCCUAUGAGCAAGUGGCAAAGGCCCUCAAAUAAGCCCCUCCUGGGACUCCCUCAACCCCCUCCAUUUUCUCCACAAAGGCCCUGGUGGUUUCCACAUUGCUACCCAAUGGACACACUCCAAAAUGGCCAGUGGGCAGGGAAUCCUGGAGCACUUGUUCCGGGAUGGUGUGGUGGAAGAGGGGAUGAGGGAAAGAAAUGGGGGGCCUGGGUCAGAUUUUUAUUGUGGGGUGGGAUGAGUAGGACAACAUAUUUCAGUAAUAAAAUACAGAAUAAAAAUCAAGUGUUUUUACGCAA